GAAUUCUAACGGCUGAGCUCUUGGAAGACUUGGGUCCUUGGGUCGCAGGUGGGAGCCGACGGGUGGGUAGACCGUGGGGGAUAUCUCAGUGGCGGACGAGGACGGCGGGGACAAGGGGCGGCUGGUCGGAGUGGCGGAGCGUCAAGUCCCCUGUCGGUUCCUCCGUCCCUGAGUGUCCUUGGCGCUGCCUUGUGCCCGCCCAGCGCCUUUGCAUCCGCUCCUGGGCACCGAGGCGCCCUGUAGGAUACUGCUUGUUACUUAUUACAGCUAGAGGGUCUCACUCCAUUGCCCAGGCCAGAGUGCGGGGAUAUUUGAUAAGAAACUUCAGUGAAGGCCGGGCGCGGUGGCUCAUGCCCGUAAUCCCAGCAUUUUCGGAGGCCGAGGCUGGAGUGCAAUGGUGUGAUCUCAGCUCACUGCAACCUCUGCUUCCUGGGUUUAAGUGAUUCUCCUGCCUCAGCCUCCCGAGUAGCUGGGAUUACAGGUGACUGCCACCACGCUCAGCUAAGUUUUGUAUUUUUAGUAGAGACGGGGUUUCACCAUGUUGGCCAGGCUGGUCUCGAACUCUUGACCUCAGGUGAUCCGCCCACCUCGGCCUCCCAAAAUGCUGGGAUUACAGGUGUAAGCCACCAUGCCCGGCCUAAAGAGGACUUUUUUAAGGUAGCAGGUAUGCCAGUAGGCUGCACAGGGAUGGAAGUGAUCCAUUAGAGGAGAGAUGAUGGAGCAGCAAGACCAUCAGGAGUGAAGACUCCGUGACAGAGGAUGGGACGCAGUGCCCAAGGGGAGGUUGGCCUUGCAGGGAAAGCACAUGCCUGUCCCUCCCUCAUUAGCUUCAUUUGGACAAAACAUGUAAAAUCCGGCAUCAUGGACCGAUCUAAAGAAAACUGCAUUUCAGGACCUGUUAAGGCUACAGCUCCAGUUGGAGGUCCAAAACGUGUUCUCGUGACUCAGCAAUUUCCUUGUCAGAAUCCAUUACCUGUAAAUAGUGGCCAGGCUCAGCGGGUCUUGUGUCCUUCAAAUUCUUCCCAGCGCAUUCCUUUGCAAGCACAAAAGCUUGUCUCCAGUCACAAGCCGGUUCAGAAUCAGAAGCAGAAGCAAUUGCAGGCAACCAGUGUACCUCAUCCUGUCUCCAGGCCACUGAAUAACACCCAAAAGAGCAAGCAGCCCCUGCCAUCGGCACCUGAAAAUAAUCCUGAGGAGGAACUGGCAUCAAAACAGAAAAAUGAAGAAUCAAAAAAGAGGCAGUGGGCUUUGGAAGACUUUGAAAUUGGUCGCCCUCUGGGUAAAGGAAAGUUUGGUAAUGUUUAUUUGGCAAGAGAAAAGCAAAGCAAGUUUAUUCUGGCUCUUAAAGUGUUAUUUAAAGCUCAGCUGGAGAAAGCCGGAGUGGAGCAUCAGCUCAGAAGAGAAGUAGAAAUACAGUCCCACCUUCGGCAUCCUAAUAUUCUUAGACUGUAUGGUUAUUUCCAUGAUGCUACCAGAGUCUACCUAAUUCUGGAAUAUGCACCACUUGGAACAGUUUAUAGAGAACUUCAGAAACUUUCAAAGUUUGAUGAGCAGAGAACUGCUACUUAUAUAACAGAAUUGGCAAAUGCCCUGUCUUACUGUCAUUCGAAGAGAGUUAUUCAUAGAGACAUUAAGCCAGAGAACUUACUUCUUGGAUCAGCUGGAGAGCUUAAAAUUGCAGAUUUUGGGUGGUCAGUACAUGCUCCAUCUUCCAGGAGGACCACUCUCUGUGGCACCCUGGACUACCUGCCCCCUGAAAUGAUUGAAGGUCGGAUGCAUGAUGAGAAGGUGGAUCUCUGGAGCCUUGGAGUUCUUUGCUAUGAAUUUUUAGUUGGGAAGCCUCCUUUUGAGGCAAACACAUACCAAGAGACCUACAAAAGAAUAUCACGGGUUGAAUUCACAUUCCCUGACUUUGUAACAGAGGGAGCCAGGGACCUCAUUUCAAGACUGUUGAAGCAUAAUCCCAGCCAGAGGCCAAUGCUCAGAGAAGUACUUGAACACCCCUGGAUCACAGCAAAUUCAUCAAAACCAUCAAAUUGCCAAAACAAAGAAUCAGCUAGCAAACAGUCUUAGGAAUCGUGCAGGGGGAGAAAUCCUUGAGCCAGGGCUGCCAUAUAACCUGACAGGAACAUGCUACUGAAGUUUAUUUUACCAUUGACUGCUGCCCUCAAUCUAGAACGCUACACAAGAAAUAUUUGUUUUACUCAGCAGGUGUGCCUUAACCUCCCUAUUCAGAAAGCUCCACAUCAAUAAACAUGACACUCUGAAGUGAAAGUAGCCACGAGAAUUGUGCUACUUAUACUGGUUCAUAAUCUGGAGGCAAGGUUCGACUGCAGCCGCCCCGUCAGCCUGUGCUAGGCAUGGUGUCUUCACAGGAGGCAAAUCCAGAGCCUGGCUGUGGGGAAAGUGACCACUCUGCCCUGACCCCGAUCAGUUAAGGAGCUGUGCAAUAACCUUCCUAGUACCUGAGUGAGUGUGUAACUUAUUGGGUUGGCGAAGCCUGGUAAAGCUGUUGGAAUGAGUAUGUGAUUCUUUUUAAGUAUGAAAAUAAAGAUAUAUGUACAGACUUGUAUUUUUUCUCUGGUGGCAUUCCUUUAGGAAUGCUGUGUGUCUGUCCGGCACCCCGGUAGGCCUGAUUGGGUUUCUAGUCCUCCUUAACCACUUAUCUCCCAUAUGAGAGUGUGAAAAAUAGGAACACGUGCUCUACCUCCAUUUAGGGAUUUGCUUGGGAUACAGAAGAGGCCAUGUGUCUCAGAGCUGUUAAGGGCUUAUUUUUUUAAAACAUUGGAGUCAUAGCAUGUGUGUAAACUUUAAAUAUGCAAAUAAAUAAGUAUCUAUGUC